ACUCCCUCCUUCACGGGCUCCAUGUCACCAUCUGUGGCACAGUCCCUCUCUGUCACUCUCCCUGCCACCCCCUCAUUCUCCUUCCUCCCUCCUGCCUCUCUCUGCAUCUCUCCCUCUCACCCGUGUCUCCUCUCCUCUCUUUCCUUCUCGUCUUCUCCCUGUCACGCAUCUCUCAUCACUCCCCCUCAUUCUGCCUUUCCUCCUACUCACGGUCUCCUCUCCCUCUCCCUCUCUCUCUCUCCCCCUCCCUCUUUCUCUCUCUCUCUCUUUCUCCACCUCCUCCCGACCCCCUUUCCCCUCUAUUUCUAUUGGCUUCUGUGUCCCUUGCUCCCCUCUUCUCUUCCUCACCCUGGGAAGCUUCUCCCCCCUAUCCUUGCCCCUGCCCCCCCAGGAUGUGUCCUGGAGAUGGGGGGUGACGUACCAGGCUCUGGUUGGGAAGUCAGGGCCGGAGACCAGAUGGGAGAGGCUCUGUGGACAGCCGUGGCCGAGGGCCUGGGAGGGAACCUGAGCCCGCAAGCGGUCUAGAAGUGGGUGCCUUGUGGGGACCCUAGUUAGGAGUGCCCUGGGGGCACCUGGGGACUGGGCAGGGAGAGGGGACAGCAGAAUGAUAACCAGCCUGGCGGCAAGGAGGGAAGCCCUCACCCCAUGGGCAGUCCUCCAAGGAGUCCGCCCCCAGCUUUCAGGCAAGCUUGUGCCAAAGAUAAACCAGACAGGGAGGAAAAGUCCCUCCUUCUCAAGGAUGAACUAGAUCAUGCACAGGAUUCCAGCUCUAAAGAAAAGACGGCACCUCAAUUGCAGGCAAAUAGCUGACUGCUGACCACCCUCCCCUCAGCCAUGGACAUGCUUCAUCCAUCAUCGGUGUCCACGACCUCAGAACCUGAGAAUGCCUCCUCGGCCUGGCCCCCAGAUGCCACCCUGGGCAACGUGUCGGCGGGCCCAAGCCCGGCAGGGCUGGCCGUCAGUGGCGUUCUGAUCCCCCUGGUCUACCUGGUGGUGUGCGUGGUGGGCCUGCUGGGUAACUCGCUGGUCAUCUAUGUGGUCCUGCGGCACACGGCCAGCCCUUCAGUCACCAACGUCUACAUCCUCAACCUGGCGCUGGCCGACGAGCUCUUCAUGCUGGGGCUGCCCUUCCUGGCCGCCCAGAACGCCCUGUCCUACUGGCCCUUCGGCUCCCUCAUGUGCCGCCUGGUCAUGGCGGUGGAUGGCAUCAACCAGUUCACCAGCAUAUUCUGCCUGACUGUCAUGAGCGUGGACCGCUACCUGGCCGUGGUACAUCCCACCCGCUCGGCCCGCUGGCGCACAGCUCCGGUGGCCCGCACGGUCAGCGCGGCUGUGUGGGUGGCCUCAGCCGUGGUGGUGCUGCCCGUGGUGGUCUUCUCGGGAGUGCCCCGCGGCAUGAGCACCUGCCACAUGCAGUGGCCCGAGCCGGCGGCGGCCUGGCGAGCCGGCUUCAUCAUCUACACGGCCGCACUGGGCUUCUUCGGGCCGCUGCUGGUCAUCUGCCUCUGCUACCUGCUCAUCGUGGUGAAGGUGCGCUCAGCUGGGCGCCGGGUGUGGGCACCCUCGUGCCAGCGGCGGCGGCGCUCCGAACGCAGGGUCACGCGCAUGGUGGUGGCCGUGGUGGCGCUCUUCGUGCUCUGCUGGAUGCCCUUCUACGUGCUCAACAUCGUCAACGUGGUGUGCCCACUGCCCGAGGAGCCUGCCUUCUUUGGGCUCUACUUCCUGGUGGUGGCGCUGCCCUAUGCCAACAGCUGUGCCAACCCCAUCCUUUAUGGCUUCCUCUCCUACCGCUUCAAGCAGGGCUUCCGCAGGGUCCUGCUGCGGCCCUCCCGCCGUGUGCGCAGCCAGGAGCCCACUGUGGGGCCCCCGGAGAAGACUGAGGAGGAGGAUGAGGAGGAGGAGGAUGGGGAGGAGAGCAGGGAGGGGGGCAAGGGGAAGGAGAUGAACGGCCGGGUCAGCCAGAUCACGCAGCCUGGCACCAGCGGGCAGGAGCGGCCGCCCAGCAGAGUGGCCAGCAAGGAGCAGCAGCUCCUACCCCAAGAGGCUUCCACUGGGGAGAAGUCCAGCACGAUGCGCAUCAGCUACCUGUAGGGGCCUGGGGAAAGCCAGGAUGGCCCGAGGAAGAGGCAGAAGCCGUGGGUGUGCCUAGGGCCUACUUCCCAAGGUGCCACAGGCCCAUGAUGGGAUGUUGAGGGGCCUGGACUUUGAUGCUAUUGCUGCCAGGUCUUGCUGUGUGACCUUGGGUAGGUUGCUUCUACUCUCUGGGCCUUGUUUUCUCCUCUGUGACUCAGGGAUAGGAGUCAUCAGCCUGGAUGAGCUAUGUCAGAUGAGAGGUUUGGAGGGCACUGUUGCUGGGCUGACCUGGCUGAGCAGGCAAAAGGUGGGUGCAGACUGGCCUCCCCCCAGGGAUGGAGUGUCUUGGGGCAUCAACUAGAAUCUUGGCCCUCAGAGGGAUAAACCAAGGCCAGGAUUUCUUGGGCUCAGAGUCAGGAACACAGGAGCUGCUGGGGGCUGGGCUGGAAACCUAAACAGAAGAAAGCCUAACCCGGUGGGAGGAGUGGGGCAGAAAUGGUCAGGCCCCAGAUCAGCUCCCUCCCCUCGACUGUGAGGCCUUGGACCAGCUCUGCUCCUCUCUAGGCCUCAGGCUUCACCUGGGUAAAACCCAACAACCUCUACACCCUUUUGGCCCAGGCAGUCAAUGCUGGAGGUCCUGUGCUCCUGGACGGGAAGAGCAGGUGAAUUUCCUGCUCAUGGAAGCGAAUGAAGUCCAGCUUCAGGGUCUCUCACUGCCUGGGCUUUUGCAAGGCCCUGCAUCUACUUUUGUACUUGUCAUUUUGUAUUCGUUUUCUUAAAGAGGGACCUCGAACUGCAUAAGCUUAGGCCACCCAAAGCCUGGCUCUGCCCCUGCUGAGGUCAGCCACCCAAUCCCCAAGGAAGCUCAUGUUGGGUCUUAUGGCUGGAGUAGGGGCCCCCGGGGGUUCCCAGGUCUUUUGAGGGCUUCCAGGCACCUCCUUGUAGGAAGGGCCAUCCCUGUUCCUCUCCUUGUGACCCAUAUUCUCCCUUCCUGGAGACCGAGACAGGGACCCAGCCCAUGAGGACUGGCAUGGAAAGGCAGAGUGUCUGAAGAGCGCUGUGAGGAGAAGGAAGAGGAAGGGAGAAGAGGAAGAGGAAGGAGAAGGAAGAGGAAGACAAGGGGGAAAGGGGAGGAUGAGGAGGGGGAAGGAGAAGUACAGAUCUGUUUCCUGGAGCCGUCUUUGGCCCCCCUGGGCUGAGCUCAGUGGUAGCAUCUGUGAACCUGAGUUGCCGACAACAGCCCCACCCAACCAGUACUGAGGGAAGGACACGAUCAGGGUGGAACAGCCAGGGUGCAAUGGCAAAUGCACAGAGUACAGACAGGCACAGGGCCUGCGUCCCUGAGGGGCCUCAGAGUGCUGCCAAGAGGGCUCAGGCCUUAAUAAAGCCCUAGGGUGGAGCUGGCUACCAGGGACAUUGGGAGGACUGGGGAGCUCCCUCCCCAUGCUCUAUCAUCCUGGAGACUACAGGUCGGGAGGCCCAGGGAAGACAAGAAGAGGCUGAAGUGGGACUGUGGAGGGGGACCAUGGGGAGCAGCCACCAUCCAAGGCUGGGCCUAGACUCCCUCCCAGAGAUGGUCCCUCAGAGCUGUGGUGAGGCUGGCCCUGGGAGGGUGAGACCCCCGGUGAAAUCCUUCCGCUUCCCCACCCCUUGCAGAGGGCAGGGGUCCUCAGGGAAAGCACAGGAACCAGACUUUUGGAGACUUGGAUCUUCAGCACACCUCAGGGUCCUGGGCUGGCAUUGGCCUUCCGGGCCUCAAUUUCCCCAUCAACAAAUGGAGAUGAAUCCCAGCUUGGCUGCCUCCUGGGAUCUAACGAGAAAAUGAGUCAUGUGAGGUAACUUCCAGGCUCACUGCAAUGGGUACGGUGGGGUGUAUCAGAUUAUAAAGUGGGGGUGCCCUCCUCACCCCCAGGCUUGGCCUAUACCCCCCUCUCCAUCAAGUGGCCUCUCUGUGUCUGUCCUUUGGGGUGAGGACACUGUAGGCCAUGAGAAAUGGGCAGUUGGGGGGUCAGAGGCCAAGGGUUAGGGAGGCAGGGCUUGGGGAGAGUGUGGGACCAUCAGAAGAGAAGGAAGUUUACAAAACCACAUUUUGUGUGGAGAUGGAGGCUGGAGGCCCGGCCCUGGGACUUGGUCUGGGGUUUCUUGAGGAAGAUCUGAGGGUCCAAGGGAGGAAGGAUGCCCUGGCCUUCUGGCCUUCUCUGGCUGAUCCUGCCUUCUUGCUGCCUAGGACAGGAGAGUAAUGUCCUAGAAUGGUCCCUGGGAGGCCAGUUAGGAAACCCUUUGCUGCUUCUGUCUCUAGCUCUUGUCAAUAAAGACGGUGACACCUGA